GACUGUGAGUCAGGAUGGCAGAGGAAGGUGAUGUGGACGAGGCGGAUGUGUUCCUGGCAUUUGCCCAGGGUCCCUCCCCUCCCAGGGGUCCCGUGCGACGUGCCUUGGACAAGGCUUUCUUUAUCUUCCUGGCCCUCUUCCUGACACUGCUGAUGCUGGAGGCUGCUUAUAAGCUGCUGUGGUUACUACUAUGGGCAAAGUUAGGGGACUGGCUCCUGGGGACACCUCAGAAGGAGGAGGAGCUGGAAUUGUGACCACCUUUCCUAUAAACAUCUUCUUUCCCCACCAAGGAGCUCACCUCUGGACCCAGCCUUGCCUCCACGAGUCCCUCCAGCCUCCCUAAACACAACGAGCAGCCCUCGCAGCGGCAAUUUGCACAAACUCUCCUCCAAGCCCCACCCCAUCAUCGCCCAUCCGCAGACCCUAGGCCUCCCACGACAAAGCACGGCCACCUGGUCAGCACAGACGGCCCUUCGAGGACCCCCUCUGGAGAAGAACCAUUCAGGUCCCAACGGUCUGGCUGGUCAUUAGUUCUGUGGUGAAGCUUGAAAAGCAAAUCAGCAACAAUAGUAAUAACAAUAACACUUUUA